ACCUUCACGCGGAGCCCAUCGGAACUCGAGGCGGGGCUGCUGGGUCUUCCAGGAGCGCCCAGACGCGGGCAGGUGGCCGCCGGUGGCCACAGGCCUGGGCAGGAUGGAAGCGCCCGCAGAGCGGGCGCUUCCACGUCUGCAGGCUCUGGCUCGGCCGCCGCCACCCAUAAGCUACGAGGAGGAGCUUUACGACUGCCUGGACUACUACUACCUGCGCGACUUCCCGGCCUGCGGGGCAGGGCGCAGCAAGGGCCGGACUCGGCGCGAGCAGGCGCUGCGCACCAACUGGCCUGCACCUGGCGGGCACGAGCGCAAGGUCGCGCAGAAGCUCCUCAAUGGCCAGCGCAAGCGCCGCCAGCGCCAGCUGCAUCCCAAGAUGCGCACUCGCCUCACCUGAGCCUGGGAUACCGAAGGACCUGUUCGAAGUAUUUACUGUAACUCCAACUGUAACUUGGUUCUGAGGAGGAGAGAAUCCAUGUUUGGUCAACAGAACUUUUCGCUGUCACUUAAGUUUACUGCUUCGAUAUCUUUUCCUUACUAAUUGAUUGUUAAUUAAGUAGUGCCCAAGUGGAUUAGCCUUUUUAGAGUUUAUUAAUUAAAAGAGAGCAGCAAGAAUGGCA